GGAGCCGGCGCCGGGAGCGGUAGCGGGAGAGCGGCAGCGGGACCCCAGCGCGGGCGGCGGCGGCUGGGCGGGAGCCCCAGAGGUACUGGCGGGAGCAGGGGACGGGAGGCACUACUGUCGGGCCCGACAGGGGAGAGGUGGCCUAGCCGUGGGCCCGGGUGAUGUGUAUGGGAGUGGGGUCCUCGCCACGUUCGCCGCCAGCACCCUCCCAACUUCCCUCCGGGCUCCAGCUCAGUCCCGAGUCAAUAUGUCCAGCCCCCUGUCUCUGACCAGCCGUUCCUACUCUCUCUGUGUGACGGCUUAGCCUGGCCAGCCAGCCGGCGGCCUCCACCCCAGUCCCUGGCCUGGCCUGGGAGGAAACAUCUGUCGCGCCCCCUGGCAGCCGAAAUGGGGUCAUGACCUCCAGAUGUGCUGGGAAGUGGCCAGCUCCUCCUCCUGGGGCAGCCAGGCCUUCCGGAUCUGUGGGGGCGGGGCCGGCCCUUUCCCCCCACCCCUAGUGACACAGGCCCGGAGGAAUGUCCUAGCCUCAAUGGACCCUGUGUGAAGCUUCAGGGUGGGGGGCAGAGCCCGAGAACACCCCUCAAGGCAGCGCCAGAGCCUGGCACUGGGCCACAGCAAGAGGCAGCGCACAGGCUGGGUGCACACAUGCACAGAUCUCACUUCCAAGCGUGCAGAGCUCAGCCCACAAGGAGCGGGGCUUGCACAGACCCCCUCCCUCAUGCCCUCCUACUCCUUCACACACUAUAGCCCAGGCCCGAGCGCUGAAUGUGCCCAGAGCUUGGCUCAUGGAGCCAGGGGCUACACCCGUCACACACACACAUAGCUAGCGACACUCACCUCAUUCUUCUCAGUCUCUCAGCAGCCUUGGGAGGGGACAGAAAUAAUUAAACCCAAUUUUUUUCUUUGUUUUUUUGGAGACAGUCUCACUCUGUCCCGCAGGCUGGAGUUCAGUGGCGCGAUCUCGGCUCACUGCAACCUCUGCCUCCCAGGUUUAAGCGAUUCUCCUGCCUCAGCCUCCUGAGUGGCUGGGACUACAGGUGCGCACCACCACACCCGGCUAAUUUUUAUGUUUUUAGUAGAGACAGGGUUUCACCAUGUUAGCUAGGCUGGUCUUGAACUCCUGACCUCAGGUGAUCCCCCCGCCUUGGCCUCCCAAAGUGCUGGGAUUACAGGCCACAGCCACCGCACCCGGCCAGUUAACCCCAUUUUAGAGAUGAGAAAACAGAGGCUCAAGGUCAGCAUGGGAGUUUAUUCAGGAGAAAUCAAGGUAGAAGCACCUGGGCUGGGGAGCCGACUCUUGCUUGGUUCUGGAGGCCCCAGACGAAGGGUGUGUGGAGCCCCUCCUCCACCCCCCUCCGGCCCAGCCCCGCAUGAUGUUGCUGGAUGCUGCAUGAAGACCCACCAUUAGAUGCCUGUACCCCCAGUGGAGGUUCCCCAGCUCCCUGUCCUCACUGCCUACUCCAUCCAGGGCUUGCCUGGGUGUGGCUUCCCUCAAGUUCUCACACCACCAUUUGCACCUGCCUCUGGCGUCACGUUUCCGCACUUAGCAGGUCCCUGGGGCUUUGGGUGUCUCAAUCUUGCAUCCUGUGAGACCUUGAACCUCAGCCCAACACCCACCCCCCAAAACCUACGCACACAGACAGCAGUGGGCAGGUGCAGCCCUGCUUAGGGCCUGGAGAUGGGCAGACCCAGGCUCACAUCCUAGCUCUGACACGGAAUUGCUUCAGGCAAGAGCAUCUCCUCUGGACCUCAUCUGACCAUCUGUCACAUGGGGUUCAGACCUCCCUGUCUGCAUCAGUGAGACCAGGUAGGCAGAGGUCCCUAUGGGUCCCUGUCAUUGUGACUCCUCUUGCCCCCAAGCCUGGGCACAGUAGCCUGCAAGAAGGUGAGUUGGCCUGUCCUUCAGGGCAGGGUGACUGGGGUCCCAUGACAGCUGCUGUGACCCCAGCACCUUCCUCAGGAUGUGGGGGCCUGGCAGAGGGCUGGGCCCACAGUUGGGGCUACUUCCUGUGCUGAAGGAAGUCCUCUUGCCAUUCCUGCUGCCCUGCCGCUGCCUCCCUGGGAACCCAUGUGUCCUUGUGGUAUUGAGGCCUUGAGGUCCAGGGCACUGAGAUCAGACCUCUCUGGGUGAUCAGCUCUCCAGGGACCCUGAAGGAAGUGGGAGGGGCAAGGAGGAAGGUCUCUGGGGACAGGACGUCCUCCCUUUGUUAAGUGGGCAGGACCCAGACACCAGUGGCCCCUGGGUUUCCCGUCCCAGCCAAUACAAGUCAUCUGUCCGGUUGGGCUAGGUCCUGGUGGGACCCUUACUCUGGGCCCAGGCCAAAGCUAAGGUGUGUGGGUGGCGACUGGGGGACCCUGGCAGUCCCAGGGCUGCCCAGGCUCCAGGACCCUCAGGACCAAGACCCAACAGCCCAGCCUCUAGCCUUGCCCAGCUAAGCUGGGGAGGGGGCUGGAAACUUUAGCCCUAGGCAGACAAGGAAGUGGCCUGGAAAGCGGAAGCAGCUUUGAUGGUCUCGGAGGGGGCCGGAAGCCAACACGGGUGGUGGAGGACCAGGCUGGGGGCCUGGGUUCCUGUUUUCUGCCCAGGCCCCUCUGAGCAGCCCCCUCCUCCUUCAGGGCAGGAACUGCUGCCACAACCUCAGGCUGGGCACCAAACACCCGUGCCCGCCAAUGCGGCCCAGCCCCCGGAGAGUCAGGCCCACAGAGCAUGCCCAUGUGGGCCGGCGGUGUGGGGAGCCCUCGGCGGGGCAUGGCCCCUGCGUCCACAGAUGACCUCUUUGCCCGCAAGCUGCGCCAGCCAGCAAGGCCCCCGCUGACACCGCACACCUUCGAGCCGAGGCCAGUCCGGGGCCCACUCCUGCGCAGCGGCAGCGAUGCAGGCGAGGCCAGGCCCCCCACGCCAGCCAGCCCCCGUGCCCGUGCCCACAGCCACGAAGAGGCCAGCCGACCUGCAGCCACUUCCACCCGGCUCUUCACUGACCCGCUGGCACUGCUGGGGCUGCCAGCAGAGGAACCAGAGCCUGCCUUCCCACCAGUGCUUGAGCCUCGAUGGUUUGCCCACUAUGACGUGCAAAGCCUGCUCUUUGAUUGGGCUCCGAGGUCUCAGGGGAUGGGGAGCCACUCAGAGGCCAGCUCUGGGACCCUGGCUUCAGCCGAGGACCAGGCUGCCAGCUCGGACCUGCUGCAUGGGGCACCUGGCUUUGUGUGUGAGCUCGGGGGUGAGGGUGAGCUAGGCCUGGGUGGACCAGCAUCCCCACCUGUGCCCCCUGCACUGCCCAACGCGGCCGUGUCCAUCCUGGAGGAGCCACAGAACCGAACCUCGGCCUACAGCCUGGAGCACGCAGACCUGGGUGCUGGCUACUACCGCAAAUACUUCUAUGGCAAAGAACAUCAGAACUUCUUCGGGAUGGACGAGUCGCUGGGCCCGGUGGCAGUGAGCCUGCGGCGGGAGGAGAAGGAGGGCAGCGGAGGGGGCACCCUGCACAGCUACCGCGUCAUCGUGCGGACCACGCAGCUCCGGACACUCCGUGGCACCAUCUCGGAGGACGCGCUGCCGCCGGGGCCCCCACGGGGUCUGUCCCCAAGGAAACUUCUGGAGCACGUGGCGCCGCAGCUGAGCCCCAGCUGCCUGCGCCUGGGCUCAGCUUCACCCAAGGUACCACGGACGCUGCUCACACUGGAUGAGCAAGUGCUGAGCUUCCAACGCAAGGUGGGCAUCCUGUACUGCCGGGCGGGCCAGGGCUCGGAGGAGGAGAUGUACAACAACCAGGAGGCGGGACCGGCCUUCAUGCAGUUUCUCACCUUGCUGGGCGAUGUGGUGCGGCUCAAAGGCUUUGAGAGUUACCGGGCCCAGCUAGACACCAAAACGGAUUCCACAGGCACGCACUCCCUCUACACCACAUACCAGGACCACGAGAUCAUGUUCCACGUGUCCACGAUGCUGCCUUACACCCCUAAUAACCAGCAGCAGCUCCUCCGGAAGCGCCACAUUGGCAACGACAUUGUGACCAUCGUGUUCCAGGAGCCUGGCAGCAAGCCCUUCUGCCCCACCACCAUCCGCUCGCACUUCCAGCACGUGUUCCUAGUGGUGCGGGCACACACACCCUGCACGCCACACACCACCUACAGGGUGGCCGUGAGCCGCACCCAGGACACCCCUGCCUUCGGGCCAGCUCUGCCUGCUGGCGGAGGCCCCUUCGCAGCCAACGCCGACUUCCGGGCCUUCCUGCUGGCCAAAGCGCUGAAUGGUGAGCAGGCGGCCGGCCACGCGCGCCAGUUCCACGCCAUGGCCACGCGCACCCGCCAGCAGUACCUGCAAGACCUGGCCACCAACGAGGUGACCACUACGUCGCUGGACUCGGCUUCACGCUUCGGCCUGCCCUCCCUGGGUGGGAGGCGCCGGGCGGCCCCUCGGGGCCCAGGCGCCGAGCUGCAGGCAGCGGGCUCACUGGUGUGGGGAGUGCGCGCGGCGCCCGGGGCGCGGGUCGCCGCCGGGGCUCAGGCGAGCGGCCCCGAAGGCAUCGAGGUGCCCUGCCUGCUGGGCAUCUCGGCCGAGGCUCUGGUGCUGGUGGCGCCGCGCGACGGCCGCGUAGUGUUCAAUUGCGCCUGUCGCGACGUGCUGGCCUGGACCUUCUCCGAGCAGCAGCUGGACCUGUACCACGGCCGCGGGGAGGCGAUCACGCUGCGCUUCGACGGGUCCCCCGGCCAAGCCGUGGGCGAGGUGGUGGCGCGCCUGCAGCUGGUGAGCCGUGGCUGCGAGACCCGCGAGCUGGCGCUGCCCCGCGACGGUCAAGGCCGCCUGGGCUUCGAGGUGGACGCCGAGGGAUUCGUCACGCACGUGGAGCGCUUCACAUUCGCCGAGACGGCGGGGCUGCGGCCCGGGGCGCGCCUCCUGCGCGUGUGCGGCCAGACUCUGCCCAGCCUCCGGCCCGAGGCCGCUGCCCAGCUCCUGCGCUCGGCGCCCAAGGUCUGCGUCACCGUCCUGCCCCCCGACGAGAGCGGCCGGCCCCGCAGGAGUUUUUCGGAGCUGUACACGCUGUCGCUGCAGGAGCCUAGCCGGCGGGGGGCCCCAGAUCCUGUGCAGGAUGAGGUCCAGGGGGUGACCCUGCUGCCCACCACAAAGCAGCUGCUGCACCUGUGCCUGCAAGAUGGUGGCAGUCCUCCAGGGCCUGGGGAUCUGGCCGAGGAGAGGACUGAGUUCCUGCACAGCCAGAACUCGCUGUCACCACGCAGCUCUCUGUCGGAUGAGGCCCCAGUCCUGCCCAACACCACCCCGGACCUCCUCCUGGCCACCACAGCCAAGCCAUCAGUACCCAGUGCUGACAGUGAGACACCCCUGACCCAGGACAGGCCAGGCAGUCCCAGUGGCUCUGAGGACAAGGGCAACCCGGCGCCGGAGCUGAGGGCCUCCUUUCUGCCACGUACCUUGUCUCUGCGGAACUCCAUCAGCAGGAUCAUGUCGGAGGCGGGCAGUGGGACCCUGGAGGACGAGUGGCAGGCCAUCUCGGAGAUUGCCUCUACUUGCAACACCAUUCUGGAGUCGCUGUCCCGAGAGGGACAGCCCAUCCCAGAGAGUGGAGACCCUAAGGGAACUCCAAAAUCUGAUGCUGAGCCAGAGCCUGGGAACCUCUCAGAGAAGGUCUCUCACUUGGAGUCCAUGCUCAGGAAGCUGCAGGAGGACCUGCAGAAGGAGAAGGCGGACAGGGCGGCCCUGGAGGAGGAGGUGCGGAGCCUGAGACACAACAACCGGCGGCUGCAGGCGGAGUCUGAGAGUGCAGCCACACGCCUCCUCCUGGCCUCCAAGCAGCUGGGCUCACCCACCGCCGACCUGGCCUGAGCCGUCUGGAACCACCUGGGCCCCUGAGGGCACUGUGGUCACACUGGGCCCUCCUCAGGAACUCUCCCUGCGCAGAGGCGUGUCUUAGCACUGCCCCCCUCCCUAGCCCCUUAUUUGGUGGCGGAAGUGGCCUCCACCCCUUCCCUGUUUGUAAAUAUUCUGUGGAGAAAAGAGGACUUCAGGGAGUAAAAAAGCCA